GGGACCUCGCGGACUGCUGUGGCGGCAGCUGGAGCGGCGGCCGCGGUGGCAGAACCGGGGGCGGCCGCUGCAGUCUGGAGCCCCAUAGUGCGGGGCCGCGGCCAGGCCACAGGAAGAGCUCGAGGCCCGGGCCGCACCGGCUGAGUGUGCGGGCCCGCGCGGCUCGGAGCCGCCGCCGCCCAUCGAGCCCCUCCGGGCGCGGGUCGGCCCGCCAUGGGGUCCCUGUUCCGGAGCGAGACCAUGUGCCUGGCGCAGCUCUUCCUGCAGUCGGGCACGGCCUACGAGUGCCUCAGCGCCCUGGGCGAGAAAGGCCUGGUCCAGUUCCGAGACCUCAACCAGAACGUAAGUUCUUUCCAAAGAAAAUUUGUUGGUGAGGUGAAGAGGUGUGAAGAGCUAGAGCGAAUAUUGGUGUAUUUGGUACAGGAAAUUAAUAGAGCUGAUAUUCCCCUUCCUGAAGGAGAGGCCAGCCCUCCUGCGCCACCCCUGAAACAGGUUCUAGAAAUGCAGGAGCAGUUGCAGAAGCUCGAGGUUGAACUGAGAGAAGUCACUAAGAACAAGGAGAAACUGAGGAAAAACUUGCUGGAACUGAUAGAGUACACUCACAUGCUGAGAGUGACAAAGACCUUUGUGAAACGCAAUGUUGAGUUUGAACCCACUUAUGAAGAAUUCCCUUCCUUAGAGAGUGAUUCUUUGUUGGAUUACAGCUGUAUGCAGAGGCUGGGAGCAAAACUGGGAUUUGUGUCUGGCCUAAUUAACCAAGGAAAAGUGGAAGCAUUUGAAAAAAUGUUGUGGAGAGUCUGCAAAGGGUACACCAUCGUGUCCUAUGCAGAACUGGAUGAAUCCCUUGAAGACCCUGAAACAGGGGAAGUCAUAAAAUGGUAUGUCUUUUUAAUAUCCUUUUGGGGAGAGCAGAUUGGCCACAAGGUUAAGAAGAUAUGUGAUUGCUACCACUGCCACGUGUACCCCUAUCCAAACACAGCCGAGGAGCGGAGGGAGAUCCAGGAGGGGCUGAACACCCGCAUCCAGGAUCUCUACACUGUACUGCACAAAACCGAGGACUAUUUGAGGCAAGUGCUAUGUAAAGCCGCCGAGUCUGUCUACAGCCGUGUGAUCCAGGUGAAGAAAAUGAAGGCCAUCUAUCACAUGCUGAACAUGUGCAGCUUUGACGUGACCAACAAGUGCCUCAUUGCUGAGGUCUGGUGUCCCGAGGCGGAUCUGCAGGACCUGCGCCGGGCACUGGAGGAGGGCUCGAGAGAGAGUGGUGCUACAAUCCCCUCAUUCAUGAAUAUAAUCCCCACAAAAGAAACACCCCCCACUCGGAUCCGCACCAACAAAUUCACCGAGGGAUUUCAGAACAUCGUGGAUGCUUAUGGAGUCGGAAGCUACAGAGAAGUCAAUCCAGCUCUCUUUACCAUCAUCACCUUCCCGUUUUUAUUUGCUGUGAUGUUUGGAGACUUCGGACAUGGCUUUGUGAUGUUUUUAUUUGCCCUCUUGUUGGUGUUAAAUGAAAAUCAUCCCAGACUAAAUCAGUCACAAGAGAUCAUGAGGAUGUUUUUUAAUGGCCGGUACAUCCUCCUGCUGAUGGGGCUGUUCUCAGUGUACACUGGCCUCAUCUACAACGACUGCUUUUCAAAGUCAGUCAACCUGUUCGGCUCUGGGUGGAACGUGUCGGCCAUGUACAGCUCCAGCCACCCACCCGCAGAGCAUAAGAAGAUGGUGCUUUGGAAUGACAGCGUCGUUAGACACAACAGCAUUUUGCAGCUGGAUCCAAGCAUUCCUGGAGUGUUCCGAGGCCCUUAUCCCCUUGGCAUUGAUCCUAUUUGGAACUUGGCCACAAAUCGCCUCACUUUUCUAAACUCUUUCAAAAUGAAAAUGUCCGUGAUUUUAGGAAUCAUUCAUAUGACUUUUGGAGUCAUUCUGGGAAUAUUUAACCACUUGCACUUCAGGAAGAAGUUCAACAUUUACCUGGUUUCCAUCCCGGAACUUCUCUUCAUGCUCUGUAUCUUUGGAUACCUUAUAUUUAUGAUUUUCUACAAGUGGCUGGUUUUUUCAGCAGAAACCUCCAGAGUUGCUCCCAGCAUUCUGAUUGAAUUUAUUAACAUGUUUUUAUUCCCAGCCAGUAAAACAAGUGGCCUUUACACAGGGCAGGAGUAUGUCCAGAGAGUGCUGCUGGUUGUCACAGCAUUGUCUGUCCCUGUCCUCUUCUUGGGAAAGCCACUGUUUUUGUUGUGGCUUCACAAUGGGCGUAGUUGCUUCGGGGUGAACCGGAGUGGCUACACACUUAUAAGGAAAGAUAGUGAGGAAGAAGUUUCAUUGCUGGGAAGCCAAGAUAUAGAAGAGGGAAAUCACCAGGUGGAAGAUGGAUGUAGAGAAAUGGCGUGUGAAGAGUUUAAUUUUGGAGAAAUAUUAAUGACCCAAGUAAUCCAUUCCAUCGAGUACUGUCUGGGAUGCAUCUCCAACACCGCCUCCUACCUGAGGCUCUGGGCGCUUAGCCUGGCUCACGCACAGUUGUCUGAUGUCCUGUGGGCCAUGCUGAUGCGCGUGGGCCUCCGCGUUGACACCACCUAUGGCGUCUUGCUACUGCUCCCGGUUAUCGCGCUCUUUGCAGUUUUGACCAUUUUCAUCCUUCUGAUCAUGGAAGGGCUUUCUGCGUUUCUUCACGCCAUACGCCUCCACUGGGUAGAAUUUCAGAACAAAUUCUACGUUGGUGCAGGCACCAAAUUUGUUCCUUUCUCAUUCAGUCUACUUUCAUCAAAGUUCAAUAACGACGACAGUGUGGCAUGAUCAUAUUGCUGUAACCAACAAGCUUUCAGAUUUAUGGAGAAUGACCAUGUUAUAGACUUUCACUUAUGUCAGAUUUAUGAUAGGAAAAAUUCCAUCUUCAUUACUGCCUUAUGACAUAGCCAAAUAAUUCUGUAAGAUAUACCUCUUCCUCAUAUGUUAAAUAUUUUGUAAAGUUUACCAAUUUGAGAUAUAAAAAUUUCUUUUGGUUUUUUAUGAUGAGCAAAUAUAAGUUAAUGCCAAACGUUAUGUUAAAGUUAUUUUUUCAAAUACAGGAUUUGGGGAGAGAAGCCAAUUUUGCAUGGCUAGUUGAAAAUGGUAUUAGAUACUUAUUUCCUUUAAACUUUAUUUAAAACAAACAACAGAGUUAAUCUGUCACCUGAAGUUGCCAGAUAAUAUUUUCCAACAGCUGAAGUAGGGAUAGUUUUUUAAAAAAUUUAAUGAUGGGUAAUCAAAACAUUCACAUUUAUUCUGCUGGAUUUAAAAAUAUGUACUUUUUUUUUUUUUUUGAGAUGAAGUCUUGCUGUGUCACGUAGGCUGGAGUGCAAUGGCACGAUCGUGUCUCAUUGCAACUUCCGCCUCCUGGAUUCAGGUGAUUCUCCUGUCUCAGCCUCCCGAGUAACUGGGAUUACAGGCAUGCGCCACCGUGACCAGCUAAUUUUUUUGUAUUUUUGUAGAGAUGGGGUUUCACCAUGUUGGCCAGGCUGGUCUCGAACUUCUGACCUCAAGUGAUCCACCUGCCUCGGCCUCCCUAAGUGCUGGGAUUACAGGCGUGAGCCACCAUGCCUGGCCAAAAUAUGCAAAUAUUUUUUAUCCUGUGCUACCUAGAAUUACAAGUAGAGGAUUGUUUUUACAAUUUUGUCUUGUUUUAGUAAUUGGGGACAAUGGGAUAAAAUGACAUACAACAAAUGGUUAUCCCACUUGUAUAUUUUUUUAAAGACUCUUAUCCUGUUACCCUUACAUAAAACCAGUUAUGAUAAUUGUAUGUUUGGAAGAUAAAUUGUAUGCUGAGCCUUAAAACCCAGUGUGACUGUAGAAGAUAUAAUGCGGACAUGAUUUGAAUUUAGUGACAGCUUGGCUGAUGUCACUGAACCAGAAGGGUUUAUACUGAGUGAAGGAAAGGUAAAAAGUAGUAUUUUGUAUAUUUUUGUAACAAAAUAUAAAUGAAGAUAUUUUACCAUGAAGAGAUUGCACUUAUCCUUGAGAACAGUCUAAAUAUAAAUGAAGAUAUUUUACCAUGAAGAGAUUGCACUUAUCCUUGAGAACAGUCUAAUGAUACUUUUUUUACUUUCAGACUGUUUCUAGCUAAAGUUCUGAUAAAAGUAUUGAGUUAAUUUAAACUUUCAAACACUGUUUAGAUCAGUUGAAAACUAAUUCUUAAUAGCCAUUGUUUUAUAAUCUUUAGUUUAAAUUCAUCUGUUUGACAUUUGGUUUUUUGUGAACUUGAGUCAGUCCUAUUGAACAUUUUGACCUAUAUUCUUGCAAAUUAUGUUAAUUUUUCAUAUUUUAGUUUGAUUUUAGACAAUUAUUUUCAAAAAGAAACCUGACUUUUUUUCACCUUCUUGACAUUGUGAGUGAUACACGUUAAAAGGCUAUUUGCCCGCAUCCUCCUCUAUCCUGUUUCGAGGUAGAGAGCUUGGCACUUCUGUUACAAGCUGAGAGUCUGGAGGUGCUGAGUUUAACGUGGCUGUGCAGCUGAUUUCAAGGCAUGAGCUGAACAGCGUUGACACAGCCGUGACUUACAAUUAAACCCUUUCAAUUACAGUACAGAUUCUGUGUGCUACUUGAUGAGAUGUUACCCAAGGCCAGUUUGGACUUACUGCUUUUUGUCCCUCAUAUUAAAUUAUCAAAUGAUGCCGAUGAAAUGCUUGAAAAUGAUUCUGCUCUCAAAGUUAUGCUUCCCUAGAAAGGUGUCAUGUCGGGCACUUGUGUUGGGUGACUAUGACAUCCCAGCAGUGCUGGUCAGGUCUCAGAGUUGCUUUCACCUAGAGCUGAUGCUUCCACAAGGGGACAUUUGUGUUACUUUGCUCCAGGGGUCUGUCAUAAAAACAAUGGUAACUACUUCAUCCCUAGGAAGCCCAAGACUUCAGGGCACUGUUAGCUGAUUGGUAAAUAAGGGACACGAUAUUCACGGGAAUUGUUUACUGCUCCCCACUAGUAAUUCUCAUGGGGCCACUUUUUUAACUCUUUCUAAUUAACACCUCUUCUCAGCAUAGAGCAGAGGAUGCAGUCAUUUCUCUGUUGAAAUCUAUGUAGUAUUUAUGUAGAAUGUCAUUAUAUGAAAAGCGAAUUCAGAAUCCUAACUCUGGGAAAGCGCUCUCUGGAAAUGUAGUUUGAUAAUAGUGUCUUAUAGGGGCCACGGGAAUUUGUUUCUCUAUAAAGCGAUGGGCUCCAGUGUCAUGUUACCAGAGUUAUCGCUCAGUUUUGUUUGUUAAGGCUUUUGCUAGAACCUAUUAUGUAUCCAGUUUUUAAAACAUACUUCAUUCCCUUGAUAGCAGAGAUCCAGAGCACAGAUGGCAAGUUGUGUGGAUGAUACUGAAUAUGUUUAUUUUCCUAAAGAUAAAUGUCACGACACGACAUUUCUCAGUUUUUAUUUAGAUGUUUAUUACCAUGUGUUAACAGAAUCUUAAAACCCAAGGGAUUUCUUCAGUAAACUAGACUUUGAUUCAACCUGCUGGGCUGGAGACUGUAAUUGCCGUGGUCAGUUAAGGAGUGCAAAGGGUGUUCUGUCUGAUAGGAUCUGGGUGAGCCCUGCGGACUUUCCAGCAGCGAAAGGACUUGGAACUCCUCUUUCGCUGAAUGCUGCUCUGUUUCUGGAAUGGAUAUUUUAUAACAACAUUCUGGUGUCAGCAUCCCCUCAGCAGUUGUUUAUUUAAAAAUUUUUUUAUUUUUUUUGAGACAGUGUCUCACUCUGUCACCUAGGCUGAAGUGCAGUGGUGCAGUCUCGGCUCACUGCAACCUCUGCCUCCUGGGUUUAAGCAAUUCUCCUGCCCUAGCCUCCCGAGUAGCUGGGAUUACAGGCGCCUGCCACAGUGCCCGGCUAAUUUUUGUAUUUUUAGUAGAGACAGGGUUUCACCAUGUUGGCCAGGCUGGUCUCAAACUCCUGACCUCAGGUGAUCUACCCACCUUGGCCUCCCAAAGUGCUGGGAUUACAGGCGUGAGCCACCGCGCCUGGCCCUCUGCAGUUGUUUAAUAAGGCACAGAAUACCUGUAGCAUAGGUCAGCCUUACGAUGUCCAUGAAUUACAUAUUCAGACGUUUUAGAGCCUGAUACAUUUUGGAAAAGAAAAACAACUUCUACACCUAUUCUACAGUCCGCAUUUAAAACAAUAAAUUCCUCUAUUAAAAACGUAAAGCCGGGUUUGCUUGCGUGCCACAGGGAAUAUAUCCAGGAAGGUUAUUAUGAAGCUGUCAAAUCAAGAUGAUGGGAAUAAGGCAGUUUGAACGAACAGUCUUCCCACAGUCAGGCCAUUUUUGCUGAUUUGGUUUAGAAUUUUCAGAAAUACUUAGUACACUCCACCUGUUCUUUGAUGGGAAUAUCUAAGAAGGCUAGGUAGGUUCUUAGGGUUAGCCUGAGUCAUCUAGGGGCUCAACUCCUUGUGAGGGGAAAUGACAGUGAACAAGUUAGUACUUUGCUCCACAAAUGCAUGAAAGGACAAAUUUGCAUCUUCUAUCAGUAUUUAACUUCCUUUUGCUAAUGACAAAUAAAUAUAUCUAUAUUUUUAAA